AAACGGCCGGCCUGGCCGCCCAACGCAGCAUUUCCAGCCAGGGCGCACAAACCUCGGGAGAGAAGGUGGAAGCCGCAGGGGCUCUAAAGGCAGCCCCAGGUUGGCUAAAGCGGUUCCUGGUACGGACACCAAGGCCCCCGUGCUCGGGCCCUACCCAGCCUGGUUCAGGCCUGUCAUACUCGUCUUUCUCUUUCCUGGGAAAUUGCUGAUGGUUCAAGUAAAGACUCUGAAGCAGUCUCAGGGAUAUACUGCUUGGUAGUAAAAGUCAAGUCUUCAUCAUCUAGUUUACGGCAUGAAUCAACACACAGUUGUUUGAAAAUGCUGAAUGCAGAUUUGUCAGAACUCCCUGAAUCUUCUGCACUUGCUCCUCCUUCUCUCAAACUUGCAUUCUUUGAUGCUUCUGGAUUGUCAUUUUGAAGACCAUUUUCAAGUAUCUUUUUUUUUAUGUUGCAAAAUUUGUUGUUGAAUGCUAGUCAAAACACCACAAAUAGCAUAAUUGUUUGCUGUCUGUCCAUACAUAUCUUGAAUAAAGACAGUAAUAUUUUGUUGAAGAAUGCCAACUAUACCUAACGAGCCAUAAUGUACAGCAGGCGUGAAGGCUGUUCCUCUCAACCUAUCAACAGCAUGUGCAUUUGCUUGUUUCUUCACUAAAAAUUCCAGCAUUUGCUGUCUUUUGCAAACUGCAGCAAGUAAAAGUGGUGUGUUUCCAUCAUUGUUCAGCACUUCAAUAUCCGUAUCAUGGGAAAAUAGUUUUUCUACCAGGAAUGUACUCUCAUUAUAGGACAGCAUAGUGGAGAGCAGUGUUGCUGUAGACAUCCACGUUCCAGCAGAACGAUGCCACAAAUCUCUUCCUGGCAAUGUACAGCCUCCUCAAAGGCAUCCCAUUUUGUUUAUCACCAAUGUCAAUGUGGCAUUUUCAGUUCACCAGGAGAGUCCCCACUUCCACAUGGCCAUUGGCACAGGCCAAACGUACAGCAGCCCUGUCCAUCCACAGCUGAAGGGAUAGAGAAACUGCCAUACAGAUACACACAGAGUAUGCUUCAGCCAUAAAGCUUUGGGAAAUCCUGUCAUUCGCAGCCACAUGGAGAAACCCAGAGGACAUUAGGUCCAAGAAAAUGAGCCUGGUGGAGCAAGUCCCACACUGCGUGACCUCAGGCAUGUGGACUCCAAAAAGCUUUAUCUCCUGCCCAUCCACAGAUGAAGGGAUCAAGAAACUCUGAUAUAUAUACACAAAGGAAUGUUCUUUGGCCAUCAAGAUAAUUAAAGGAUGUCAUUUGGAGGAACAUAGAUGGCCCGCCGAGGCUGCGGCUGCCUCAUCCUGCACUGUGGAUGGAAGCCGCUGAUCUGACAGGAAGUGGAGCUCAGGUGGUAAUGCUCGCUCUUGCUGUGCUGCCAGGUUCUUAACAGGCCAGGGAUGAUACUGGUCCAGGGGUGGGGGAGCCCUGCUCCAGAUGACAGCCAGAGUAGUCUUAAAUUCCUCCUUUGUAUAGCCUUGGAAAACAGAUCAGCGAGGUAGCAGUGAAAGACAUCAUGAUACCAAAUAGAAACAAGGACUUGGAAGACACAUUGGACCUCUUAAUUUCCAGGCCACUUGAUAGUAGAUACAGUUCCUUACAAAAGAACAUGGCUUCAUCUUGGGAAAAGAGGGUGCUGGAGGUGAGGGAAGAUGAAUUAGCCACCAAGACAGUUCACCUUGCAAUUCAAUCAUUUAGGUCUAACUGGAGAAUGAUUGCUGCCAUGUUCCAGAACAAGAAUGAAAGCCUCGUUUCACAAUGAAAAGGGGCUGGCCUCCAAUGAUUGGUCGCUGCCGCGAGGGCCGCCGGGACUCGCACUCGGCGGUUGUUCCAGAAGAAAGAGACAGCGAUGGCGGCAGAGGCUUCGAAGACUGGGCCUUCUAGGUCUUCCUACCAGCGAAUGGGGAGGAAGAGUCAGCCCUGGGGUGCCGCUGAAAUCCAGUGCACCAGGUCACCAUUGUGAACUUCAAUGUGGACAUGCUUUUUGUGAACUAUGCUUGUUAAUGACUGAAGAAUGCACCACAAUUAUAUGCCCUGAUUGUGAGGUUGCUACAGCUGUAAAUACUAGACAACGCUACUACCCAAUGGCUGGAUAUAUUAAGGAAGACUCCAUAAUGGAAAAACUGCAGCCUAAGACGAUAAAGAAUUGUUCUCAGGACUUUAAGAAGACUGCUGAUCAGCUAACUACUGGUUUAGAACGUUCAGCCUCCACAGACAAGACUCUUUUGAACUCAUCAGCUGUAAUGUUGGACACUAAUACUGCAGAAGAAAUUGAUGAAGCAUUGAAUACAGCACACCAUAGUUUCGAACAGUUAAGCAUUGCUGGAAAAGCACUUGAACACAUGCAGAAGCAAACGAUAGAGGAAAGAGAAAGAGUUAUAGAAGUUGUGGAGAAACAGUUUGACCAACUUUUGGCUUUUUUUGAUUCCAGGAAAAAGAACCUGUGUGAAGAAUUUGCAAGAACUACUGAUGAUUAUCUAUCAAAUUUAAUAAAGGCUAAAAGCUACAUUGAAGAGAAAAAAAAUAAUUUGAAUGCAGCUAUGAACAUAGCAAGAGCAUUACAAUUAUCGCCUUCUCUAAGAACAUACUGUGACCUGAAUCAGAUUAUCCGGACUUUGCAGUUAACUUCAGAUAGUGAAUUAGCACAAGUUAGUUCUCCACAACUAAGGAACCCUCCCAGGUUGAGUGUGAAUUGCAGUGAGAUCAUCUGUAUGUUCAACAAUAUGGGAAAGAUUGAAUUUAGGGACUCAACAAAAUGUUAUCCCCAAGAAAAUGAAAUUAGACAGAAUGUUCAAAAGAAAUAUAAUAACAAAAAGGAACUUUCUUGUUACGAUACAUACCCACCGCUAGAAAAGAAAAAGGUUGACAUGUCUGUCCUAACCAGUGAAGCACCACCACCUCCUUUGCAACCUGAGACAAAUGAUGUACAUUUAGAAGCAAAAAACUUCCAGCCACAGAAAGACGUUGCAACAGCAUCCCCUAAAACCAUUGCUGUGUUACCUCAGAUGGGAUCUAGCCCUGAUGUGAUAAUUGAAGAAAUUAUUGAAGACAACGUGGAAAGUUCUGCAGAGCUAGUUUUUGUAAGCCAUGUAAUAGAUCCUUGCCAUUUCUACAUUCGGAAGUAUUCACAAAUAAAAGACGCCAAAGUACUGGAGAAGAAGGUGAAUGAAUUUUGCAAUAGGAGUUCACACCUUGAUCCUUCAGACAUUUUGGAACUAGGUGCAAGAAUAUUUGUCAGCAGUAUUAAAAAUGGAAUGUGGUGUCGAGGAACUAUCACAGAAUUAAUUCCAAUAGAGGGUAGAAAUACCAGAAAACCUUGUAGUCCAACCAGAUUAUUUGUCCAUGAAGUUGCACUAAUACAAAUAUUCAUGGUAGAUUUUGGAAAUUCUGAAGUCCUGAUUGUCACUGGAGUUGUUGAUACCCAUGUGAGACCAGAACACUCUGCUAAGCAACAUAUUGCACUAAAUGAUUUAUGUCUGGUUCUAAGGAAAUCUGAACCAUAUACUGAAGGGCUGCUAAAAGACAUCCAGCCAUUAGCACAACCAUGCUCAUUGAAAGACAUUGUUCCACAGAAUUCAAAUGAAGGCUGGGAAGAGGAAGCUAAAGUGGAAUUUUUGAAAAUGGUAAAUAACAAGGCUGUUUCAAUGAAAGUUUUUAGAGAAGAAGAUGGUGUGCUUAUUGUAGAUCUGCAAAAACCACCACCGAAUAAAAUAAGCAGUGAUAUGCCUGUGUCUCUUAGAGAUGCGCUAGUUUUUAUGGAACUAGCAAAGUUUAAGUCACAAUCACUAAGAAGUCACUUUGAAAAAAAUACUACUUUACACUAUCAUCCACCUAUUUUGCCUAAAGAAAUGACAGAUGUUUCAGUAACGGUUUGUCAUAUAAAUAGUCCUGGAGAUUUCUAUCUUCAGUUGAUAGAGGGCCUGGAUAUUUUAUUUCUAUUAAAGACAAUCGAGGAAUUCUAUAAAAGUGAAGAUGGAGAAAAUCUGGAAAUCCUCUGUCCAGUUCAAGAUCAAGCCUGUGUAGCUAAAUUUGAAGAUGGAAUUUGGUACCGAGCAAAAGUUAUCGAACUUAACCAUUGGGAAUCUUGCUGGAAAAGUUGUAUAGAUAGAACAAAGCAACAGAAAUUAAUUAUUCAAAAACCGGUGAACUCUAGUUUGAUGUUGACUGUUUGUCUGUCCCAUGCUAUUUUGAUUGUCAAGGUACAAAUUAAAGGAUUGCCUGGACAUCAGGAAGUUGAAGUUAAAUAUGUGGACUUUGGUAAUACUGCAAAAAUAACAAUCAAAGACGUGCGUAAAAUAAAGGAUGAGUUUCUGAAUGCCCCAGAGAAGGCAAUUAAAUGUAAGUUGGCCUAUAUUGAACCAUAUAAAAGGACAAUGCAGUGGUCCAAAGAAGCUAAAGAAAAAUUUGAAGAAAAGGCUCAAGAUAAAUUUAUGACAUGUUCAGUUAUCAAAAUUCUGGAAGAUAAUGUGCUCUUAGUUGAGCUUUUCGAUUCUCUUGGUGCUCCUGAAAUGACUACUACUAGUAUUAAUGACCAGCUAGUUAAAGAGGGCCUAGCAUCUUAUGAAAUAGGAUACAUCCUCAAAGAUAAUUCUCAAAAGCAUAUUGAAGUUUGGGAUCCUUCUCCAGAAGAAAUUAUUUCAAAUGAAGUACACAACUUAAAUCCUGUGUCUGCAAAAUCUCUACCUAAUGAGAAUUUUCAGUCACUUUAUAAUAAGGAAUUGCCUGUGCAUAUCUGUAAUGUAAUAUCUCCUGAGAAGAUUUAUGUUCAGUGGUUGUUAACUGAAAACUUACUUAAUAGUUUAGAAGAAAAGAUGAUAGCUGCUUAUGAAAACUCAAAAUGGGAACCUGUUAAAUGGGAAAAUGAUAUGCACUGUGCUGUUAAGAUCCAAGAUAAAAAUCAGUGGCGAAGAGGCCAGAUCAUCAGAAUGGUUACAGACACAUUGGUAGAGGUCUUGCUGUAUGAUGUGGGUGUUGAACUAGUAGUGAAUGUUGACUGUUUAAGAAAACUUGAAGAAAAUCUAAAGACAAUGGGAAGACUCUCUUUGGAAUGUUCUCUGGUUGACAUAAGACCAGCUGGUGGGAGUGACAAGUGGACAGCAACAGCUUGUGACUGUCUUUCAUUGUACCUGACUGGAGCUGUAGCAACUAUAAUCUUACAGGUGGAUAGUGAGGAAAACAACACAACAUGGCCAUUACCUGUGAAAAUUUUCUGCAGAGAUGAAAAAGGAGAGCGUGUUGAUGUUUCUAAAUAUUUGAUUAAAAAGGGUUUGGCUUUGAGAGAAAGGAGAAUUAAUAACUUAGAUAACAGCCAUUCAUUAUCUGAGAAGUCUCUGGAAGUCCCCCUGGAACAGGAAGAUUCAGUAGUUACUAACUGUAUUAAAACUAACUUUGACCCUGACAAGAAAACUGCUGACAUAAUCAGUGAACAGAAAGUGUCUGAAUUUCAGGAGAAAAUUCUAGAACCAAGAACCACUAGAGGGUAUAAGCCACCAGCUAUUCCUAACAUGAACGUAUUUGAGGCAACAGUCAGCUGUGUUGGUGAUGAUGGAACUAUAUUUGUAGUACCUAAACUAUCAGAAUUUGAGCUAAUAAAAAUGACAAAUGAAAUUCAAAGUAAUUUAAAAUGCCUUGGUCUUUUGGAGCCUUAUUUCUGGAAAAAAGGAGAAGCAUGUGCAGUAAGAGGAUCCGAUACUCUGUGGUAUCGUGGCAAGGUGAUGGAGGUUGUAGGUGGCGCUGUCAGAGUACAAUAUUUAGAUCAUGGAUUCACUGAAAAGAUUCCGCAGUGCCAUCUUUACCCUAUUUUGCUGUAUCCUGAUAUACCCCAGUUUUGUAUUCCUUGUCAGCUCCAUAAUACCACACCUGUUGGGAAUGUCUGGCAACCAGAUGCAAUAGAAGUUCUUCAACAACUGCUUUCAAAGAGACAGGUGGACAUUCACAUUAUGGAGUUACCUAAAAAUCCAUGGGAGAAAUUGUCUAUUCACCUCUAUUUUGAUGGAAUGUCACUUUCUUAUUUUAUGGCAUACUAUAAAUACUGUACUUCUGAACAUACUGAGGAGAUGUUGAAAGAAAAACCAAGAUCAGAUCAUGAUAAAAAGUAUGAAGAGGAACAAUGGGAAAUAAGGUUUGAGGAAUUGCUUUCGGCUGAAACAGACACUCCUCUUUUACCACCAUAUUUGUCUUCAUCUCUGCCUUCCCCAGGAGAACUCUAUGCUGUUCAAGUUAAGCACGUUGUCUCACCUAAUGAAGUGUAUAUUUGCCUUGAUUCUAUAGAAACUUCUAACCAGUCUAACCAGCAUAGUGACACAGAUGAUAGUGGAGUCAGCGGGGAAUCAGAAUCCGAGAGCCUUGAUGAAGCACUGCAGAGGGUUAAUAAGAAGGUAGAGGCGCUUCCUCCUCUGACGGAUUUUAGAACAGAAAUGCCUUGCCUUGCAGAAUAUGAUGAUGGCUUAUGGUAUAGAGCGAAGAUUGUUGCCAUUAAAGAAUUUAAUCCUUUAUCUAUCUUAGUACAAUUUGUUGAUUAUGGAUCAACUGCAAAGCUGACAUUAAACAGACUGUGCCAAAUUCCUUCUCAUCUUAUGCGGUAUCCAGCUCGAGCCAUAAAGGUUCUCUUGGCAGGGUUUAAACCUCCCUUAAGGGAUCUAGGGGAGACAAGAAUACCAUAUUGUCCCAAAUGGAGCAUGGAGGCACUGUGGGCUAUGAUAGACUGUCUUCAAGGAAAACAACUCUAUGCUGUGUCCAUGGCUCCAGCACCAGAACAGAUAGUGACAUUAUAUGACGAUGAACAGCAUCCAGUUCAUAUGCCGUUGGUAGAAAUGGGGCUUGCAGAUAAAGAUGAAUAAGUGCCUAAGUAUUAAAAACUCAAGAUGUGAAUGCAAAAGCGCAUAGAAGAAAAUGGUGUACUUGUGGCCUGAGGAUUGAGAAGAAUUAAAGUCAUGAAAACCAAAAACUAUUUUAAAAGACUAGUAAAUUCAACAUUACAAGGAAAAACAUACAUUAAAAAAAACACAAACUGAAAAGCCAAACCCAGAUUGGGAGAAAAUAUUAGCAGUGCUUGUAACUGACAAAGGAUUACUAUGCGGAAUAUUUUAUAAGGAGAAACACACACACACACAUCCAAAAUUUUAAAUGGACAAAGGAAAUGAACAGGCAGUUCACAAAAGGGGAACCUCAAAUGCUGACUAAAUGUAAGAAAACAUGCUCACAGGGCCUUACCAGCUCACGGAAUCAACCACCAUUUUACAUCAACUGGCCAAAAUGUUAAAGUCUGGCCAGAUCAAGUGUUUGCAAGUAUGAAGAGCAUACUCUGCUGACAGUAAA